AAACAGUGCUACCCACAGAGUGAACAAGAGAGAGUCAUUUGGGAAACAAAAGGAGAAUUUUACAGAGAGAGAGGGAUAGCUAAAACUACGUGAGCCUGGCGAGGGUGCAGAGCAGAAAGUAGAGACUGUCCGAAGACUGCUAUCUGGGACGAGACAAGUUGUUAAAGGGACAGGAGAGAAAGCAGAGCUAUUUCAAGAGUGAGCCACAGAAGGGAAUCCAGAGGCCAUCUAAGCGAGGAAGGGUCUACAGGCAGUGAGUGAAGGCCAGGAGCAGGGCCCAGGCCAGGCACGACCACCGAGGGGAUGAACUUCACAGUGGGUUUCAAGCCGCUGCUAGGGGAUGCACACAGCAUGGACAACCUGGAGAAGCAGCUCAUCUGCCCCAUCUGCCUGGAGAUGUUCUCCAAACCAGUGGUGAUCCUGCCCUGCCAACACAACCUGUGCCGCAAAUGUGCCAACGACGUCUUCCAGGCCUCGAAUCCUCUAUGGCAGUCCCGGGGCUCCACCACUGUGUCUUCAGGAGGCCGUUUCCGCUGCCCAUCGUGCAGGCAUGAGGUUGUCCUGGACAGACACGGUGUCUACGGCCUGCAGCGAAACCUGCUAGUGGAGAACAUUAUCGACAUUUACAAGCAGGAGUCAUCCAGGCCGCUGCACUCCAAGGCUGAGCAGCACCUCAUGUGCGAGGAGCAUGAAGAAGAGAAGAUCAAUAUUUACUGCCUGAGCUGUGAGGUGCCCACCUGCUCUCUCUGCAAGGUCUUCGGUGCCCACAAGGACUGUGAGGUGGCCCCACUGCCCACCAUUUACAAACGCCAGAAGAAACAGGAUCUCACUCUGUUGCCCAGGCUGGAGUGCAGUGGCACAAACACAACUUACUGCAGCCUUGAUCUCCCGAGCUCAAGUGAUCCUCCCAUCUUAGCCUCGCAGAACACUAAGAUUAUAGAUAGUGAGCUCAGCGAUGGCAUCGCGAUGCUGGUGGCAGGCAAUGACCGCGUGCAAGCAGUGAUCACACAGAUGGAGGAGGUGUGCCAGACUAUCGAGGACAAUAGCCGGAGGCAGAAGCAGUUGUUAAACCAGAGGUUUGAGAGCCUGUGCGCAGUGCUGGAGGAGCGCAAGGGUGAGCUGCUGCAGGCGCUGGCCCGGGAGCAAGAGGAGAAGCUGCAGCGCGUCCGCGGCCUCAUCCGUCAGUAUGGCGACCACCUGGAGGCCUCCUCUAAGCUGGUGGAGUCUGCCAUCCAGUCCAUGGAAGAGCCACAAAUGGCGCUGUAUCUCCAGCAGGCCAAGGAGCUGAUCAAUAAGGUCGGGGCCAUGUCGAAGGUGGAGCUGGCAGGGCGGCCGGAGCCAGGCUAUGAGAGCAUGGAGCAAUUCACCGUAAGGGUGGAGCACGUGGCCGAAAUGCUGCGGACCAUCGACUUCCAGCCAGGCGCUUCCGGGGAGGAAGAGGAGGUGGCCCCAGACGGAGAGGAGGGCAGCGCGGGGCCGGAGGAAGAGCGGCCGGAUGGGCCUUAAGGCCUGCGCCGACCCGACCCUGCUCGAGAGCCCGCGCUAGAGUCGGGGAGGAUCUGCGCAGAGACCGCAGCAUCACCCAAAUCGGCGCCGGCCCCGGGAGGAUCUCAAUAAAGAACUCGAGCGUCCCAGACCCGUAUCUCCUUUCGCUGCCCAACCCCGCAGCCUGGGCUUCGAAGGCGACCCGCCCACCAUCCUGCCCUUCCCAGAACCUGAGACCGUCUGGGGGGCGGAAGCCAAAUGAACCCCUAUUGGGCACCUCUGUGAUGCCAGGAGCGAACUGGUGAGCCCAGCGCCCUGGGAAGAGGGCCGAGGGCGGGGCGGUGGUGCCGGGACCUCUGAGGUCCUGGGGAUUUGGGGACCCUUGGGGUCCACAUGCACCUGGCUGACCUGGCUGAAAGCCGCUGUCUCGGAGCCCCCCACAGCAUUUUGUUCCCCUCCCGCUGGCCCGGGGGCCCCACCUUCCCACGGGUUCCCACGCUGCUGUGACUGCCCUGCCUCUACGACAAAAGCCAACGGGUCUUCAGUACUUUUAUUAAAAAAUAGUCACGCA